AUUUUCCCAGCUUACUAGUGGAAAAGCAGCUUCUUUCCCACAGUUCCAGCAAAAGCCCCAGGGCUGAUGCUCAUUGGCCCAGGUUGGGGCAUGUGACCAUUGGCAAGACUCCCAUUGGCCAGGCCUGGGGCAGGUGCUCACUACUGGAGCCAGAGCGGAGUAUAAGCCCUACCCAAUCACUGAACUACGUGGGUCAAGAGUAAAGGAGCUGUGGCUUCCCCCCAAUCAGAAGGGCACUGGAUGAUGGAUGAACUCUGUGUGGUGCGUCUUCACACUGACACCAGGAGGAUAAGGAAGUGACUCCCUCAGCUGAGUGGCUGGCAUGUGCCAGGCUAGAGCAGCUUGGCUAUGGCAGAACAUCCAGCCCCACCGUGUGGACGGCAGAGAUGAGGAAACUGGUGUGGGGUUGCCGGGGCCAGCAACCACUUUUCUAAAGCCAAAGACGCAGAAGGUGCUGCCAGUCCAACGCUUCCUCCAUGGAGGCCUUCACCCACCCACACCCAUCUAAGAGUUCCCAAGACCUGUUUUUUCUGGCUAUUCCUAGACAGCCAUCACCCCCACUCACAUGUCUUCCACAAGGGCGGCCAGGCGGCCAGGCUGCAGGAGGAGUGUGACUAUGUGCAGAUGAUCGAGGUGCAGCACAAGCAGUGCCUGGAGGAGGCCCAGCUGGAGAAUGAGACAAUAGGCUGCAGCAAGAUGUGGGACAACCUCACCUGCUGGCCAGCCACCCCUCGGGGCCAGGUAGUUGUCUUGGCCUGUCCCCUCAUCUUCAAGCUCUUCUCCUCCAUUCAAGGCCGCAAUGUAAGCCGCAGCUGCACCGACGAAGGCUGGACGCACCUGGAGCCUGGCCCGUACCCCAUUGCCUGUGGUUUGGAUGACAAGGCAGCGAGUUUGGAUGAGCAGCAGACCAUGUUCUACGGUUCUGUGAAGACCGGCUACACCAUUGGCUACGGCCUGUCCCUCGCCACCCUUCUGGUCGCCACAGCUAUCCUGAGCCUGUUCAGGAAGCUCCACUGCACGCGGAACUACAUCCACAUGCACCUCUUCAUAUCCUUCAUCCUGAGGGCUGCCGCUGUCUUCAUCAAAGACUUGGCCCUCUUCGACAGCGGGGAGUCGGACCAGUGCUCCGAGGGCUCGGUGGGCUGUAAGGCAGCCAUGGUCUUUUUCCAAUAUUGUGUCAUGGCUAACUUCUUCUGGCUGCUGGUGGAGGGCCUCUACCUGUACACCCUGCUUGCCGUCUCCUUCUUCUCUGAGCGGAAGUACUUCUGGGGGUACAUACUCAUCGGCUGGGGGGUACCCAGCACAUUCACCAUGGUGUGGACCAUCGCCAGGAUCCAUUUUGAGGAUUAUGGGUGCUGGGACACCAUCAACUCCUCACUGUGGUGGAUCAUAAAGGGCCCCAUCCUCACCUCCAUCUUGGUAAACUUCAUCCUGUUUAUUUGCAUCAUCCGAAUCCUGCUUCAGAAACUGCGGCCCCCAGAUAUCAGGAAGAGUGACAGCAGUCCAUACUCAAGGCUAGCCAGGUCCACACUCCUGCUGAUCCCCCUGUUUGGAGUACACUACAUCAUGUUCGCCUUCUUUCCGGACAAUUUUAAGCCUGAAGUGAAGAUGGUCUUUGAGCUCGUCGUGGGGUCUUUCCAGGGUUUUGUGGUGGCUAUCCUCUACUGCUUCCUCAAUGGUGAGGUGCAGGCGGAGCUGAGGCGGAAGUGGCGGCGCUGGCACCUGCAGGGCGUCCUGGGCUGGAACCCCAAAUACCGGCACCCGUCGGGAGGCAGCAACGGCGCCACGUGCAGCACGCAGGUUUCCAUGCUGACCCGCGUCAGCCCAGGUGCCCGCCGCUCCUCCAGCUUCCAAGCCGAAGUCUCCCUGGUCUGACCACCAGGAUCCCAGGGGCCCAAGGCGGCCCCUCCCGCCCCUUCCCACUCACCCCGGCAGACGCCGGGGACAGAGGCCUGCCCGGGCGCGGCCAGCCCCGGCCCUGGGCUCGGAGGCUGCCCCCGGCCCCCUGGUCUCUGGUCCGGACACUCCUAGAGAACGCAGCCCUAGAGCCUGCCUGGAGCGUUUCUAGCAAGUGAGAGAGAUGGGAGCUCCUCUCCUGGAGGAUUGCAGGUGGAACUCAGUCAUUAGACUCCUCCUCCAAAGGCCCCCUACGCCAAUCAAGGGCAAAAAGUCUACAUACUUUCAUCCUGACUCUGCCCCCUGCUGGCUCUUCUGCCCAAUUGGAGGAAAGCAACCGGUGGAUCCUCAAACAACACUGGUGUGACCUGAGGGCAGAAAGGUUCUGCCCGGGAAGGUCACCAGCACCAACACCACGGUAGUGCCUGAAAUUUCACCAUUGCUGUCAAGUUCCUUUGGGUUAAGCAUUACCACUCAGGCAUUUGACUGAAGAUGCAGCUCACUACCCUAUUCUCUCUUUACGCUUAGUUAUCAGCUUUUUAAAGUGGGUUAUUCUGGAGUUUUUGUUUGGAGAGCACACCUAUCUUAGUGGUUCCCCACCGAAGUGGACUGGCCCCUGGGUCAGUCUGGUGGGAGGACGGUGCAACCCAAGGACUGAGGGACUCUGAAGCCUCUGGGAAAUGAGAAGGCAGCCACCAGCGAAUGCUAGGUCUCGGACUAAGCCUACCUGCUCUCCAAGUCUCAGUGGCUUCAUCUGUCAAGUGGGAUCUGUCACACCAGCCAUACUUAUCUCUCUGUGCUGUGGAAGCAACAGGAAUCAAGAGCUGCCCUCCUUGUCCACCCACCUAUGUGCCAACUGUUGUAACUAGGCUCAGAGAUGUGCACCCAUGGGCUCUGACAGAAAGCAGAUACCUCACCCUGCUACACAUACAGGAUUUGAACUCAGAUCUGUCUGAUAGGAAUGUGAAAGCACGGACUCUUACUGCUAACUUUUGUGUAUCGUAACCAGCCAGAUCCUCUUGGUUAUUUGUUUACCACUUGUAUUAUUAAUGCCAUUAUCCCUGAAUCCCCCUUGCCACCCCACCCUCCCUGGAGUGUGGCUGAGGAGGCCUCCAUCUCAUGUAUCAUCUGGAUAGGAGCCUGCUGGUCACAGCCUCCUCUGUCUGCCCUUCACCCCAGUGGCCACUCAGCUUCCUACCCACACCUCUGCCAGAAGAUCCCCUCAGGACUGCAACAGGCUUGUGCAACAAUAAAUGUUGGCUUGGA